AUUAAUCAGCCACCCCUCACUAGGUGUUGGGGUUCCACCACGCUUCCUCCACCCCCCGUCACCACAGCAGCGGGUAGUAUUUAGGUUGAAUAUUCCAAAUAGUCAAUUAUGACAGUUAAUUUCAAAUGAGAUGACUUCGAAGUACACGUGAAAACAAUACUAUUUUAUAUCACGACUCAUGCCAUCCGUAUGUGUAAUCAAAGCCUUCUAAGUCUUGAUAUGUCCUUACAAAGACGAAGGAUAGAGUGAAUGUCAAAAUUUGCCAAACAGGAGUUACUGAAAGUCUGAAGGGGAAAGCCUAGUUAGGUUUUAUCUUAGAAGUGAUUUUUAAAACGAAACACGCAGAUAAGCUCGAGCUUUCUGGAGCCGAUUCCUAAGGCCUUGCAGGUGGUAAGGGGGUCGAGAAUUGGCUGAGGUUCCUCGGAAGUCCGCGCCGAUUCGGAGGGCCACCUCUGACUUUCUGAUCUGGGGUGCAACCCCCAGUCCCUGUCCCGGUCGACAAAGGUUUGCCUGCAAUGAGAUUUCAUUCUCUACAUUUAAAGGACAUCCUUUCUGAGCUGCUGUGAAUAAAUUUGGAAUGGUACUGUAUAUUUUCAUCUAAUGGAGAACUAGCUGUACUUUGAAUAAGGAUUGCUGCACUGGACGACUUUAGAACAUCCCUCACAAUGUCGUCAACCCGGAGCCAGAACCCCCACGGCCUGAAGCAGAUUGGCCUGGACCAGAUCUGGGACGACCUCAGAGCCGGCAUCCAGCAGGUGUACACACGGCAGAGCAUGGCCAAGUCCAGAUAUAUGGAGCUCUACACUCAUGUUUAUAACUACUGUACUAGUGUUCACCAGUCAAACCAAGCACGAGGAGCUGGAGUUCCUCCUUCUAAGUCGAAAAAGGGGCAGACACCUGGAGGAGCUCAGUUUGUUGGCCUGGAAUUAUAUAAACGACUUAAGGAAUUUUUGAAGAAUUACUUGACAAAUCUUCUUAAGGAUGGAGAAGAUUUGAUGGAUGAGAGUGUACUGAAAUUCUACACUCAACAAUGGGAAGAUUAUCGAUUUUCAAGCAAAGUGCUGAAUGGAAUUUGUGCCUACCUCAAUAGACAUUGGGUUCGCCGUGAAUGUGACGAAGGACGAAAAGGAAUAUAUGAAAUCUAUUCGCUUGCAUUGGUGACUUGGAGAGACUGUCUGUUCAGGCCACUGAAUAAACAGGUAACAAAUGCUGUUUUAAAGCUGAUUGAAAAGGAAAGGAAUGGUGAAACCAUCAAUACAAGAUUGAUUAGUGGAGUUGUACAGUCUUACGUGGAAUUGGGGCUGAAUGAAGAUGAUGCAUUUGCAAAGGGCCCUACGUUAACAGUGUAUAAAGAAUCCUUUGAAUCUCAAUUUUUGGCUGACACAGAGAGAUUUUAUACCAGAGAGAGUACUGAAUUCUUGCAGCAGAACCCAGUUACUGAAUAUAUGAAAAAGGCAGAGGCUCGUCUGCUUGAGGAACAACGAAGAGUUCAGGUUUACCUUCAUGAAAGCACACAAGAUGAAUUAGCAAGGAAAUGUGAACAAGUCCUCAUUGAAAAACACUUGGAAAUUUUCCACACAGAAUUUCAGAAUUUAUUGGAUGCUGACAAAAAUGAAGAUUUGGGACGCAUGUAUAAUCUUGUAUCUAGAAUCCAGGAUGGCCUAGGAGAAUUGAAAAAACUGUUGGAGACACACAUUCAUAAUCAGGGUCUUGCAGCCAUUGAAAAGUGUGGAGAAGCUGCUUUAAAUGACCCCAAAAUGUAUGUACAGACAGUGCUUGAUGUUCAUAAAAAAUACAAUGCCCUGGUAAUGUCUGCAUUCAACAAUGACGCUGGCUUUGUGGCUGCUCUUGAUAAGGCUUGUGGUCGCUUCAUAAACAACAACGCGGUUACCAAGAUGGCCCAAUCAUCCAGUAAAUCCCCUGAGUUGCUGGCUCGAUACUGUGACUCCUUGUUGAAGAAAAGUUCCAAGAACCCAGAGGAGGCAGAACUAGAAGACACACUCAAUCAAGUGAUGGUUGUCUUCAAGUACAUAGAAGACAAAGACGUAUUUCAGAAGUUCUAUGCGAAGAUGCUCGCCAAGAGGCUCGUCCACCAGAACAGUGCAAGUGACGAUGCCGAAGCCAGCAUGAUCUCCAAGUUAAAGCAAGCUUGCGGGUUCGAGUACACCUCUAAACUUCAGCGCAUGUUUCAAGACAUUGGCGUGAGCAAAGAUCUGAACGAGCAAUUCAAAAAGCACUUGACAAACUCAGAACCCCUAGACUUGGAUUUCAGCAUUCAAGUGCUGAGCUCCGGGUCCUGGCCCUUCCAGCAGUCUUGUACAUUUGCCUUGCCGUCAGAGUUGGAACGUAGUUAUCAGCGAUUCACAGCUUUCUACGCCAGCCGCCACAGUGGCCGAAAAUUGACGUGGUUAUAUCAGUUGUCUAAAGGAGAAUUGGUAACUAACUGCUUCAAAAACAGAUAUACUUUGCAGGCGUCGACAUUCCAGAUGGCUAUCCUGCUUCAGUACAACACGGAAGAUGCCUACACUGUGCAGCAGCUGACCGACAGCACUCAAAUUAAAAUGGACAUUUUGGCGCAAGUUUUACAGAUUUUAUUAAAGUCGAAGCUAUUGGUCUUGGAAGAUGAAAAUGCAAAUGUUGAUGAGGUGGAAUUGAAGCCAGAUACCUUAAUAAAAUUAUAUCUUGGUUAUAAAAAUAAGAAAUUAAGGGUUAACAUCAAUGUGCCAAUGAAAACCGAACAGAAGCAGGAACAAGAAACCACACACAAAAACAUCGAGGAAGACCGCAAACUACUGAUUCAGGCGGCCAUCGUGAGAAUCAUGAAGAUGAGGAAGGUUCUGAAACACCAGCAGUUACUUGGCGAGGUCCUCACUCAGCUGUCCUCCAGGUUCAAACCUCGAGUCCCUGUGAUCAAGAAAUGCAUUGACAUUCUAAUUGAGAAAGAAUAUUUGGAGCGAGUGGAUGGUGAAAAGGACACCUACAGUUACUUGGCUUAACCCUUCUGGAAGGGUCUGACUGUGUGACCCGCAGCAAAUAGUUCAUGUUGGAAAGAAUGAAAACAACUCAAGUUCAUAGCAGCCAGCCUGCCGCCAUUGGACCUCCCUUUUAAAAACUGAGACCAAGACUCCCAUCAGCUGGUCUCGGAUUUACAUCGGAACUGCUCAGGAUUGAUACAUUUCAAGUCUGUAAAUACGGACACCAACGCCAUUUACCCUAAUUUAAGAACAGCGGGGACUGACCCUCCGUGCCGAGGGCUGCAUGCUACCGCACUAAGUCAAUACAUGGGCUCCCCGAUUCGCAGCUGUCGUCUUGGCAGCACUUGUCACGUUGGCAGCACUUUGAGAGCAAGUCUGAGUGGACCCACAUGUAACCUGCUAUGAAAACCAUUUGUAUAGUGUGUUUCAUUUUUUAAUGUGUGAAAAUAAAGAAAAUUAAAGGAUUUCUGUACAAGUCGCAUUGGGUUUUGUUUUAAGUUUUACUAAUUUCUAUAUGUAAAUAAAAGAUAUAAUGAUUGUGCAAAUUUA